GAGGAGCGGCUCCGGCGGCCGGAGAAGGCGCAGGAGGAGGAAGAGGCGGAGGAAGAGGAGGGGAAUCGCCGCUUCCCAAACACUCUCUCCGAGGGGGCUGUGCGCGGCUCUCGGCUUUCGGCCCUCGGACGCCCGCGCCGGGAGUCCGAACCCGGGCUGUCCGCGGCCCCCUCUUCCCCCUCCUCCGCCCCGCGCAGACGAGGAACAAAGUUGCCGAGAGCGACUGGGCCGGAGGGCUGCAGCCCGGGCCGGGUGCUCUGGCCGCGGCGGCGCCGGCGCCGGGGCAGCUCCGCUCCGGGCGCGCUGAUGGGGGGAGGCGGCGGCGGCGGAGCCCACAGCGGCGGCCCGAGCAGCAGAGGCGGCGGCGGCGGCGGCUGGGCGGCCCGAGGGGAUGCAGCAGCAGUCGGGAGGGACGGCCGAGCCCAGUAGACAGAGACCAGGAGCGGCGGCCGAGGCGAUCGGGCUUCGCAGCGCCCGGACCUGAGCCAGACCCACCUGGUCCGUCCUCCCGACCGGCGGCCGAGGCGCCCGAGGACUGGGGACGCGGAAGAUCCAAGUGAUUCUCGGAGACCCCUGGGCGGCGGCUGCGCAAGCCCCUGAGAGGAGGGGGCGACCCUCAGCGCCGUGGGGGAGGAGGCUCCGCCUGCCCACAGCCCUCCCCACUGCCACUCGUACCUCCCUAAAAAUAACUCGGGCCCGCUGGGGCCAGGAGGAGCCGCCACUGUCCCCCGAGUGGAGCCGGGGAGGCGUGUCGAGCCAGGGCCGGAGGAAGCCGGCGGAGCGGCGAGGAAGAGGAGGAGGAGGAGGAAGGGGAGUUCCGCCUGCGGGCCGCAUCGCACGGCAGCCUAGGGGCGCCGCGACCCUCCCGGCUGCGUCCAGCCCCUCGCGCCUGUACCGCGCUCUCGGCCGCCGGGCCCAGCCGAGCCGCCCCCCCGCGGGCCCCGCGCCGCCGCCGCCGCGGUUUGGCUGAUUAGUCGCGGGCGGGCGGGCGGGCGCAGCGCGCAGGGCGGAGGCAGCAGCGGCGCUGGGCCGGGAGGAGGCCGGCCAGGGUGCGGAGCGGCCCCGGCCCGCUCCCAGAGGGGAGAUGGCGUCCUACGUAGAUAACAGCUUCCGCCAGGCGGUGAUGAAGAAUCCCCCCGAAAGGACCCCCCAGGAUCUGGAAAUAGUAUAUUCCUAUUUACAUGGUAUGGAAGCCUUAUCAAACUUGAGGGAGCAUCAACUUAGGUUAAUGUGUGAAACUGUGAGAUAUGAGAGACACGAAGCAAAUGAAGUUUUAUACUACCCUGAUGAUAUUGGGACCUGCUGGUAUAUCCUUCUUUCUGGUUCCGUGUUCAUCAAGGAAUCCAUGUUUCUUCCAAGAAGCAGUUUUGGCAAGCGUUCUGCAGGAAGUUUUAGGCGUGGCUGUGAAUGCAUUGUUUUAGAGCCUUCUGAAAUGAUUGUGGUGGACUAUAUGGAUGAAAAUGAAGAAUAUUUUCAGCGGCAAGCUUCCCAUAGACAGUCUCGAAGGAGAUUUAGAAAAAUCAACCAGAAAGGUGAAAGACAAACAAUUAUUGACACUGUGGAUCCUUAUCCCAUGGGCAAACCUCCUUUGCCUAGAGGCUAUCACACGGAAUGCACUAAAUCUCAGCUUCCUGCAGAUUUCACAAAACUGCAUCUUACUGACAGUCUCCACCCACAGGUGACCCACGUUUCUUCUAGCCAUUCAGGAUGUAGUAUCACUAGUGAUUCUGGGAGCAGCAGUCUUUCUGAUAUCUACCAGGCCACAGAAAGCGAGGCUGGUGAUAUGGACCUGAGUGGGUUGCCAGAAACAGCAGUGGAUUCCGAAGACGACGACGAUGAAGAAGACAUUGAGAGAGCAUCAGAUCCUCUGAUGAGCAGGGACAUUGUGAGAGACUGCCUAGAGAAGGACCCAAUUGACCGGACAGAUGAUGACAUUGAACAACUCUUGGAAUUUAUGCACCAGUUGCCUGCUUUUGCCAAUAUGACAAUGUCAGUGAGGCGAGAACUCUGUGCUGUGAUGGUGUUCGCAGUGGUGGAAAGAGCAGGGACCAUAGUGUUAAAUGAUGGUGAAGAGCUGGACUCCUGGUCAGUGAUUCUCAAUGGAUCUGUGGAAGUGACUUAUCCAGAUGGAAAAGCAGAAAUACUGUGCAUGGGAAAUAGUUUUGGUGUCUCUCCUACCAUGGACAAAGAAUACAUGAAAGGAGUGAUGAGAACAAAGGUGGAUGACUGCCAGUUUGUCUGCAUAGCCCAGCAAGAUUACUGCCGUAUUCUCAAUCAAGUAGAAAAGAACAUGCAAAAAGUUGAAGAGGAAGGAGAGAUUGUUAUGGUGAAAGAACACCGAGAACUUGAUCGAACUGGAACAAGAAAGGGACACAUUGUCAUCAAGGGUACCUCAGAAAGGUUAACAAUGCAUUUGGUGGAAGAGCAUUCAGUAGUAGAUCCAACAUUCAUAGAAGACUUUCUGUUGACCUAUAGGACUUUUCUUUCUAGCCCAAUGGAAGUGGGCAAAAAGUUAUUGGAGUGGUUUAAUGACCCGAGCCUCAGGGAUAAGGUUACACGGGUAGUAUUAUUGUGGGUAAAUAAUCACUUCAAUGACUUUGAAGGAGAUCCUGCAAUGACUCGAUUUUUAGAAGAAUUUGAAAACAAUCUGGAAAGAGAGAAAAUGGGUGGACACCUAAGGCUGUUGAAUAUCGCGUGUGCUGCUAAAGCAAAAAGAAGAUUGAUGACGUUAACAAAACCAUCCCGAGAAGCUCCUUUGCCUUUUAUCUUACUUGGAGGCUCUGAGAAGGGAUUUGGAAUCUUUGUUGACAGUGUAGAUUCAGGUAGCAAAGCAACUGAAGCAGGCUUGAAACGGGGGGAUCAGAUAUUAGAAGUAAAUGGCCAAAACUUUGAAAACAUUCAGCUGUCAAAAGCUAUGGAAAUUCUUAGAAAUAACACACAUUUAUCUAUCACUGUGAAAACCAAUUUAUUUGUAUUUAAAGAACUUCUAACAAGAUUGUCAGAAGAGAAAAGAAAUGGUGCCCCCCACCUUCCUAAAAUUGGUGACAUUAAAAAGGCCAGUCGCUACUCCAUUCCAGAUCUUGCUGUAGAUGUAGAACAGGUGAUAGGACUUGAAAAAGUGAACAAAAAAAGUAAAGCCAACACUGUGGGAGGAAGGAACAAGCUGAAAAAGAUACUCGACAAGACUCGGAUCAGUAUCUUGCCACAGAAACCAUACAAUGAUAUUGGGAUUGGUCAGUCUCAAGAUGACAGCAUAGUAGGAUUAAGGCAGACAAAGCACAUCCCAACUGCAUUGCCUGUCAGUGGAACCUUAUCAUCCAGUAAUCCUGAUUUAUUGCAGUCACAUCAUCGCAUUUUAGACUUCAGUGCUACUCCUGACUUGCCAGAUCAAGUGCUAAGGGUUUUUAAGGCUGAUCAGCAAAGCCGCUACAUCAUGAUCAGUAAGGACACUACAGCAAAGGAAGUGGUCAUUCAGGCUAUCAGGGAGUUUGCUGUUACUGCCACCCCGGAUCAAUAUUCACUAUGUGAGGUCUCUGUCACACCUGAGGGAGUAAUCAAACAAAGAAGACUUCCAGAUCAGCUUUCCAAACUUGCAGACAGAAUACAACUGAGUGGAAGGUAUUAUCUGAAAAACAACAUGGAAACAGAAACUCUUUGUUCAGAUGAAGAUGCUCAGGAGUUGUUGAGAGAGAGUCAAAUUUCCCUCCUUCAGCUCAGCACUGUGGAAGUUGCAACACAGCUCUCUAUGCGAAAUUUUGAACUCUUUCGCAACAUUGAACCUACUGAAUAUAUAGAUGAUUUAUUUAAACUCAGAUCAAAAACCAGCUGUGCCAACCUGAAGAGAUUUGAAGAAGUCAUUAACCAGGAAACAUUUUGGGUAGCAUCUGAAAUUCUCAGAGAAACAAACCAGCUGAAGAGGAUGAAGAUCAUUAAGCAUUUCAUCAAGAUAGCACUGCACUGUAGGGAAUGCAAGAAUUUUAACUCAAUGUUUGCAAUCAUCAGUGGCCUAAACCUGGCACCAGUGGCAAGACUGCGAACGACCUGGGAGAAACUUCCCAAUAAAUACGAAAAACUAUUUCAAGAUCUCCAAGACCUGUUUGAUCCUUCCAGAAACAUGGCAAAAUAUCGUAAUGUUCUCAAUAGUCAAAAUCUACAACCUCCCAUAAUCCCUCUAUUCCCAGUUAUCAAAAAGGAUCUCACCUUCCUUCACGAAGGAAAUGACUCAAAAGUAGACGGGCUGGUCAAUUUUGAGAAGCUAAGGAUGAUUGCAAAAGAAAUUCGUCACGUUGGCCGAAUGGCUUCAGUGAACAUGGACCCUGCCCUCAUGUUCAGGACUCGGAAGAAGAAAUGGCGGAGUUUGGGGUCUCUCAGCCAGGGUAGUACAAAUGCAACAGUGCUAGAUGUUGCUCAGACAGGUGGUCAUAAAAAGCGGGUACGUCGUAGUUCCUUUCUCAAUGCCAAAAAGCUUUAUGAAGAUGCCCAAAUGGCUCGAAAAGUGAAGCAGUACCUUUCCAAUUUGGAGCUAGAAAUGGACGAGGAGAGUCUUCAGACAUUAUCUCUGCAGUGUGAGCCAGCAACCAACACAUUGCCUAAGAAUCCUGGUGACAAAAAGCCUGUCAAAUCCGAGACCUCUCCAGUAGCUCCAAGGGCAGGGUCACAACAGAAAGCUCAGUCCCUGCCACAGCCCCAGCAGCAGCCACCACCAGCACAUAAAAUCAACCAGGGACUACAGGUUCCCGCCGUGUCCCUUUAUCCUUCACGGAAGAAAGUGCCCGUAAAGGAUCUCCCACCUUUUGGCAUAAACUCUCCACAAGCUUUAAAAAAAAUUCUUUCUUUGUCUGAAGAAGGAAGUUUGGAACGUCACAAGAAACAGGCUGAAGAUACAAUAUCAAAUGCAUCUUCGCAGCUUUCUUCUCCUCCUACUUCUCCACAGAGUUCUCCAAGGAAAGGUGGCAGUGGCAAUCAGCUGAGAUCUUUUGGCUCCGGGCAGUUGGACUUAACCAGUUCCUCCUCUUCUCUUGGAAGCUAUACUUUGGCUCCCAGUGGUACUGUGGAUAAUUUUUCAGAUUCUGGUCACAGUGAAAUUUCUUCACGAUCCAGUAUUGUUAGCAAUUCGUCUUUUGACUCAGUGCCAGUCUCACUGCACGAUGAGAGGCGCCAGAGGCAUUCUGUCAGCAUCGUGGAAACAAACCUAGGGAUGGGCAGGAUGGAGAGGCGGACCAUGAUUGAACCUGAUCAGUAUAGCUUGGGGUCCUAUGCACCAAUGUCCGAGGGCCGAGGCUUAUAUGCUACAGCUACAGUAAUUUCUUCUCCAAGCACAGAGGAACUUUCCCAGGAUCAGGGGGAUCGCGCGUCACUUGAUGCUGCUGACAGUGGCCGUGGGAGCUGGACGUCAUGCUCAAGUGGCUCCCAUGAUAAUAUACAGACGAUCCAGCACCAGAGAAGCUGGGAGACUCUUCCAUUCGGGCAUACUCACUUUGAUUAUUCAGGGGAUCCUGCAGGUUUAUGGGCAUCAAGCAGCCAUAUGGACCAAAUUAUGUUUUCUGAUCAUAGCACAAAGUAUAACAGGCAAAAUCAAAGUAGAGAGAGCCUUGAACAAGCCCAGUCCCGAGCAAGCUGGGCGUCUUCCACAGGUUACUGGGGAGAAGACUCAGAAGGUGACACAGGCACAAUAAAGCGGAGGGGUGGAAAGGAUGUUUCCAUUGAAGCCGAAAGCAGUAGCCUAACGUCUGUGACUACGGAAGAAACCAAGCCUGUCCCCAUGCCUGCCCACAUAGCUGUGGCAUCAAGUACUACAAAGGGGCUCAUUGCACGAAAGGAGGGCAGGUAUCGAGAGCCCCCGCCCACCCCUCCCGGCUACAUUGGAAUUCCCAUUACUGACUUUCCAGAAGGGCACUCCCAUCCAGCCAGGAAACCGCCGGACUACAACGUGGCCCUUCAGAGAUCGCGGAUGGUCGCACGAUCCUCCGACACAGCUGGGCCUUCAUCCGUACAGCAGCCACAUGGGCAUCCCACCAGCAGCAGGCCUGUGAACAAACCUCAGUGGCAUAAACCGAACGAGUCUGACCCGCGCCUCGCCCCCUAUCAGUCCCAAGGGUUUUCCACCGAGGAGGAUGAAGAUGAACAAGUUUCUGCUGUUUGAGGCACAGACUUUUCUGGAAGCAGAGCGAGCCACCUGAAAGGAGAGCACAAGAAGACGUCCUGAGCAUUGGAGCCUUGGAACUCACAUUCUGAGGACGGUGGACCAGUUUGCCUCCUUCCCUGCCUUAAAAGCAGCAUGGGGCUUCUUCUCCCCUUCUUCCUUUCCCCUUUGCAUGUGAAAUACUGUGAAGAAAUUGCCCUGGCACUUUUCAGACUUUGUUGCUUGAAAUGCACAGUGCAGCAAUCUUCGAGCUCCCACUGUUGCUGCCUGCCACAUCACACAGUAUCAUUCCAAAUUCCAAGAUCAUCACAACAAGAUGAUUCACUCUGGCUGCACUUCUCAAUGCCUGGAAGGAUUUUUUUUAAUCUUCCUUUUAGAUUUCAAUCCAGUCCUAGCACUUGAUCUCAUUGGGAUAAUGAGAAAAGCUAGCCAUUGAACUACUUGGGGCCUUUAACCCACCAAGGAAGACAAAGAAAAACAAUGAAAUCCUUUGAGUACAGUGCUUGUCCACUUGUUUACAAUGUCCUCCUUUUAAAAAAAAAAAAUGAGUUUAAAGAUUUUGUUCAGAGAGUAAAUAUAUAUCCAUUUAAUGAUUACAGUAUUAUUUUAAACCUUAAGUAGGGUUGCCAGCCUGGUUUCUGAAAAACCAAAUAUGCCGGACAGGGUGUGGCCACACCAAGAAGACGGGAAGACCUGGCUUGUGACCCUGGCUUCCCAUGUCCUUCUGGUCUCACCCGCGAAGUGCCCUAUCCUGGAAGUAUGAAAUGUUAGCCAAUUAAUACCAAGACACCUCAUCUGCUCCUUCCCCAGUGGAUGGGGUUCUUCUGUAAAACUGUUUGCACAUGGCCAGGGGAGGGAACUAGGACCCUUGUGUCCUGUCUGAGCCUUAUGGAGGCAGGACGGUGUCAUUGGCGGAUGUGUCCUGCUCCAUUGAGAUGGAUGGCAAACCCCAUUUUUAAGUUAUAUUUCUUUGAUUUUUGUUAAUUUAGAGGUGUAGGUUUUGUUUUUUGUUUUUUUGUUUUUUUUUAAGAGAAACAUUUAUAACUGGAUAGCAUUGCAGUGAAAGCAGCUUGGGAUGUUGGAGCUAAUGCCAGCUGUUUAUACUGCUCUUUCAAGACAGCCUCCCUUUAUUGAAUUGGCAUUAGGGAAUAAACAAGCCUUUAAACGUGAUAAAAGAUCAAAAACCUGGUUAGACAUGCCAGCCUUUGCAAGGCAGGUUAGUCACCAAAGACUAACCUCCAAGUGGCUUUAUGGACGCUGCAUAUAGAGAAGGCCUAAGUGUAGCAACCAUCUGCUCACAGCUGCUAUUAACCCUAUAAUGACUGAAAUGACCCCUCCACUCUAUUUUUGUGUUGUUUUGCACAGACUCCGGAAAAGUGAAGGCUGCCAAUCUGAGUAGUACUCAAAUGUGAGGAACUGCUGGUCUUGGAUUUUUUUUCCAUUAAAUUCAGCUGAUCAUAUUGAUCAGUAGAUAAACGUAAAUAGCUUCAAAUUUUAAAAGUGGAAUUGCAGUGUUUUUUCACUGUAUCAAACAAUGUCAGUGCUUUAUUUAAUAAUUCUCUUCUGUAUCAUGGCAUUUGUCUACUUGCUUAUUACAUUGUCAAUUAUGCAUUUGUAAUUUUACAUGUAAUAUGCAUUAUUUGCCAGUUUUAUUAUAUAGGCUAUGGACCUCAUGUGCAUAUAGAAAGACAGAAAUCUAGCUCUACCACAAGUUGCACAAAUGUUAUCUAAGCAUUAAGUAAUUGUAGAACAUAGGACUGCUAAUCUCAGUUCGCUCUGUGAUGUCAAGUGCAGAAUGUACAAUUAACUGGUGAUUUCCUCAUACUUUUGAUACUACUUGUACCUGUAUGUCUUUUAGAAAGACAUUGGUGGAGUCUGUAUCCCUUUUGUAUUUUUAAUACAAUAAUUGUACAUAUUGGUUAUAUUUUUGUUGAAGAUGGUAGAAAUGUACUAUGUUUAUGCUUCUACAUCCAGUUUGUACAAGCUGGAAAAUAAAUAAAUAUAACAUAAAGCCUUGCCUAUAUUCUUAAUGAA